AGAGCUGGCUGCGCCGAGCCCCCUGCGCGCUGCACAUGGGGCGCCUGACGGAAGCGGCGGCAGCGGGCAGCGGCUCUCGGGCUGCAGGCUGGGCAGGGUCCCCUCCCACGCUCCUGCCGCUGUCUCCCACGUCCCCCAGGUGCGCGGCCACCAUGGCGUCCAGCGACGAGGACGGCACCAACGGCGGCGCCUCGGAGGCCGGCGAGGACCGGGAGGCUCCCGGCGAGCGGAGGCGCCUGGGGGUCUUGGCCACCGCCUGGCUCACCUUCUACGACAUCGCCAUGACCGCGGGGUGGUUGGUUCUAGCUAUUGCCAUGGUACGUUUUUAUAUGGAAAAAGGAACACACAGAGGUUUAUAUAAAAGUAUUCAGAAGACACUUAAAUUUUUCCAGACAUUUGCCUUGCUUGAGAUAGUUCACUGUUUAAUUGGAAUUGUACCUACUUCUGUGAUUGUGACUGGGGUCCAAGUGAGUUCAAGAAUCUUUAUGGUGUGGCUCAUUACUCACAGUAUAAAACCAAUCCAGAAUGAAGAGAGUGUGGUGCUUUUUCUGGUCGCGUGGACUGUGACAGAGAUCACUCGCUAUUCCUUCUACACAUUCAGCCUUCUUGACCACUUGCCAUACUUCAUUAAAUGGGCCAGAUAUAAUUUUUUUAUCAUCUUAUAUCCUGUUGGAGUUGCUGGUGAACUUCUUACAAUAUACGCUGCCUUGCCGCAUGUGAAGAAAACAGGAAUGUUUUCAAUAAGACUUCCUAACAAAUACAAUGUCUCUUUUGACUACUAUUAUUUUCUUCUUAUAACCAUGGCAUCAUAUAUACCUUUGUUUCCACAACUCUAUUUUCAUAUGUUACGUCAAAGAAGAAAGGUGCUUCAUGGAGAGGUGAUUGUAGAAAAGGAUGAUUAAAUGAUCUCUGCAAACAAGGUGCUUUUUCCAGAAUAACCAAGAUUACCUGAGUCCAAGUUUUAAUAACAAGAAUAAACAACUUUGUGAAAUAUCAUGGAUUGUAUGGUUUCUUAAAAUAUAACUUGAGACACGUGGUAUUUGCCAGUAUUUGUGUUCCUCUUGUGCCAGAUCUAUUUUUUACAAGAACUGUGCAAAUAUCAGUAACUUUUGGGUAGGUAUUGAUUAUUAGGAAAAUAAUUAGGUGUAUUAUCUGGGGGAAAAAAAAACUUUUGCUAAGUUUUUUUUGAAACAUGCUCAAAGCUUUUUAAAUCAAUAUUUAGAAAUUAGUUUAACGAUUUACUAUUAUACCUGCUAGUGAUAUUUAUGUGAUAUUUAUAAAUGAAAAUAAAUGCAAAAUUAUAACAACUUGUUAAUAAUGUAUUGGUAUUUUUGAACCCACAAUCUAUUUUUUCAGGAAUAAGGCAGCAUUAUGACUAAUAACAGUGUUUGGAAGCGUGGAUAUAAUUUGCUAAAGUAAGACUUUUGAUGUAGAUAAAGUAGCAGCAUAAAAACACACAAAUAUUCAAGUAGAUGUCACAGUUGGAAAAUAUUCUUUGGAAAUAUUUCUAGGCAGCUGAAAUUACUUAUACUGCUAAGGAAAUCUGCUUUUUAUUUAAAUUAGCCACUUAAGGACAAGGUUUUCAACUGUGAAGGUUUUAAGGGGUUAGGAAGAGCAUAAGUAUUUGCCCCACUAUUAAAAAAAAAACAUGACAUCUGACUAUAAUGUUGUAUUCAGGCUGGGAGUGGUAGCUCAUGCCUGUAAUCCCAGCACUUUGGAAGACUGAGGCAGGAGGAUCGUUUGAGCCCAGAAGUUCAAGGCCAGUCUGGGCAACAUAGCAAGACCCCAUCCCUAAAAAAAUUACAAACAAAAAAAAUUAACCAGGCAUGGUGACACAUGCCUGUAGUUCCAGCUGCUUGGGAGGCUGAGGUGGGAGGAUCACUUGAGCCCAGGAAUUCAAGGUUACAAUGAGCUAUGAUGGUACCACUGUACUUAAGCCUGGGUGACAGAGCAAGACCCUGUCUCUGAAAAAUAGUGAUGAUGAUGAUGAUGAUGAUAACGAUGAUGAGGAAGAUGAUCAUGCUGUACUCAGAACUUUGGUUGAGAAAGUCUUCUCUAUACUGUAGAAUUAUCUUGUAACAAUUGUUAUGAUAAUCCCUUUGUGGUACUUAGGUAACUAAACAUUUUGGGGUAUGAUCUUUGGACAGACUCCUUUCAUUCUGAAUUCCAUUGAAUAGCAAAAGGUCUUGUAAUAAAGUUCCUGUCCUUGUGUUUAAUAAAAAAAAUACACCAGA